AUGAAAGCCGUAGGUGAGUUCCGACACAGCUAUUUUUUAAAAGAAAGUUUUACAGUGAAGGUGUUGGACUCCCAGCCCAGAAGGGCUCUGAUCUCAGAACUGGGACGCAAGGGUGGGGAGCUCGAGCUCUCAUUAGCAUUUCGCUUUUGCACACCCCCUGCCCGCUCCUCAGCCGUCACAAUCCCGUCCUGCAGCAGGCCCCCCCACCAACACCGGACCCUCGACGGGGAAGGGGUCAGCUCGGCGGCCCCAGAGGCCACUGGGCCAGAACACGUGCUCCGGACUCCACGUGCGCGGAAAAUGAACUCGUACCCGCGACGCGGCCGGCGGGGGCGGAUGGCAGCGAGGGCCGGACAGCGAACCUUUACCCCGCGGAGGAGUCGGGGCCGGAGCCCGCACGUGGGUCUGCGACGGCCCCGCCCCCUGGGGGCGUCCCCUCAGGGACUCUAG